GAACCGGGCUGGGCGCUCGUCGCGUAGUGGGUGGGGGCGCAGGGAGCGGGAGCCGCCGCCGCCGCCGCCGCCGCCGGAGCUAACCUCGGGGACCGAGAUGCAGGUGGGACCGGAACCGGAACCCCCCUCUUCAAGUACCUUUUCCCUCUCCGCGACCCGGCCCUGGCGCCCGAGAGGAUUCCUGGGUGGGGGUGGGCGUGGAGGGCCGGGGGCUGGAGAGGCACUCGGCCCCGGAGAGUGCAGCAGACAGGGCUGGUCCCGAGGUGGAUGCGGCCCCGGAAAAUGGGCGGCUGGGGGGUGUCCAGGGAGUAGGGUCGGAUCGGAGUAUAUGGACCACCGGGCCCGGAGGGUCCGAGCCGAGAGCGGAGCCUGCACCCUCCACCUCCCGCCCUUCGGGAAAUAUCAGAACUGAGCCAGGAGGCAGGUGCACCGGGAAAAUGUGUCUGAGUCCUGCUUGGCAGAAGAGAAACUGAGUCACCAGCUUAGGAGUCGCAGGGUCAGCGGGCCUGAAGGGGGCUGGGUCUGUCUGCGGUGCGGAGGAUUGGGUGGGCCUGUGUGAGCCGAGGUGGCCGCUGGCUGGAGAUUGGUUUGCACUUCUUGGCUGGGUUCCCCCGUGCUCCAUGACUCCUGCAUCUCCUGAUUGUUUCUCGUUGGUUUGGAGUUGUCCCUGCGGUUGGAGCCAUCUGAGCUUGUAGGGUCGAGGCCCAGGAGGAAGGGGAGGGUUCACCGACUUACAGCCUGGCUGUAGGUUUGAACAGGAGUCUGAGGUCGCUGAGGGUUUGGGGAGGCUUUCCUGAGCUGCUCUGGCCCCAGUCCUGGGGCUGUCACCUUCCAGUAUUGCGUGGCGGGAGGAGCGCUAACAAGAGCCAAGGGUUGUAAAUUCCACACCCAGCUCUGCCACUUUCUAGUUGUAAGACCUUGAGAGGGCUCCUCCUUUCUCUAAUUUCUAUUUUAGAAAAUUGGAACAAUAAUAUUCUUCUCCCACAUGAAGAUAGUAACAAUGGCAGUCGUUCAGCGGAUGCUUACUUUGCGUUCAGCGCUGACAUACCCCAUUCCAUGUAAUUCUCUCAACAUUUCGAGGGGAGGGAUCAUUAGCUUUGUUUAACAGAUAGAAAAACGGAGGCUCAGAGAGGACGUGGAAUUUGUUCAAGAUAACAUCGCUCAUAAGGUGGCUGGACUGGGUGCUCAUAAGGUGGUUUGAGCCCUGGUCUGACUCAAGUCCAUGGCCUUAACCAGAAGGCUAACCUGCCUUUAGGGCAUACUCCCCAGUGGGAGAAGAGGAAGGUGAAAAAUCCUAGGGCCCCAGCUCUCCCUGUGAUGUUUUGUUUACGUGAGGCCAGCAAAGACUUGACCUGAGCCAACCCAGUUUCUCCUCUGGGGCCCCUGCGGCCUCUGGCCCCAGACUGAAGGGAUACCAAAGAAGUGGGCUGUAGCUAUUUCACAUCUCCUUCACGCAGUGCGUGGGUGCUGGACUCUGGGGUCAGCUUUCAAGACAAUUACUGUUUUGGUCCAUCAUGCAUCCAUCCUCAUUAAUGAAUCGGCCCCCUCCAAAGAGUUGGACCCUAAGAUGCGUGAGGCAGGCUCUCUAAGGUCUAGAAUCCCAGCUCCUCUCUAGCCCCCUGCGAGCUGGGGCGGUGAGGUGCUAUGGCUGAGGCUGGCCCAGCCGGGCCCUGGGGACAGGGACUAUGAAGUGGGGAAAACAGUAGACUUGGAGUUCUGAAACUUUUCUGAGCUUCGGUUUCCUCAUCUGUUCGAGAGGUCUUUGAAACCUCUCAGGGAAAGGUAAGAUAACCAAGUGGGAGCCUCUAGAAUGGCUCAUGGGAAGUGUGACAUGAAUAUUGGAGGAUCCGAUGUAGAGGGGGGGUGAUCUGGAAAAGUUCCCUUUUUUAGGGGGAAGGUGCUCCAAAGCCCUCUACUGCUGGAUCCAAAGCUAAGGAAAGUGGGGGCAAAUGUGGCAGGCUCGGGGCAGGUUAGACGCUGGGGAGCCAGUUGGCUGGGGCCUGCAGGGUGCCAGGAUCUGGGAGAGGGAAGGGAGGUGUUGGGCUCCCUUCCCCAUUGCUCUCUGCGGAGUCUGAAGUAGGGUCGGACGUCUCUGGCUGGGGGUGGGAUGCAGCCUCCGGUGCGCCCUCAGCAGUGACCCUCGUGUGUGCCUCUCUCUUCCUUUCGCAGCUGCUGCCGCCCACCCCUCGUCUUCUGGCUGCCUCCCUCUUUGUGCCCCACAGGCUCCCCCUCUCCACCUCCUGGGGCCCAUCAUGAAUGGUGCCCCUUCCCCAGAGGACGGGGCCUCCCCCUCGUCUCCCCCGCUGCCCCCACCCCCGCCCCCUAGUUGGCGGGAGUUCUGUGAGUCCCACGCCCGGGCUGCGGCUCUGGACUUUGCCCGCCGUUUUCGCCUCUACCUGGCCUCCCACCCCCAAUAUGCGGGGCCCGGGGCCGAGGCUGCCUUCUCCCGCCGUUUUGCUGAGCUCUUCCUGCAGCACUUUGAAGCCGAGGUGGCCCGGGCCUCUGGCUCCCUGUCGCCACCCAUCCUGGCUCCCCUGAGCCCUGGUGCGGAGAUUUCGCCACAUGACCUGUCCCUUGAGAGCUGCAGGGUGGGUGGGCCCCUGGCUGUGCUGGGCCCUUCUCGAUCAUCUGAGGACCUGGCCGGCCCCCUCCCUUCCUCAGUCUCUUCCUCCUCUACAACCUCCUCCAAGCCGAAGCUCAAGAAGCGCUUUUCCCUGCGUUCAGUGGGUCGCUCUGUCCGAGGCUCAGUCCGUGGCAUCCUGCAGUGGCGGGGGACCGUUGACCCUCCCUCCUCCGCUGGGCCCCUGGAGACCUCGUCAGGCCCCCCAGUCUUAGGUGGAAACAGCAACUCCAACUCCUCUGGCGGGGCUGGGACCGUUGGUAGGGGACUGGUCAGUGAUGGAACGUCCCCUGGGGAAAGAUGGACUCACCGUUUUGAGAGGCUGAGACUCAGUCGGGGAGGGGGCGCCUUGAAGGAUGGAGCAGGGAUGGUGCAGAGGGAAGAGCUGCUGAGUUUCAUGGGGGCUGAGGAGGCAGCCCCUGACCCAGCCGGAGUGGGCCGGGGAGGAGGGGUGGCUGGGCCUCCUUCAGGGGGAGGAGGGCAGCCUCAGUGGCAGAAGUGUCGCCUGCUGCUUCGAAGUGAAGGAGAAGGAGGAGGAGGAAGUCGCCUGGAGUUCUUUGUACCACCCAAGGCCUCUCGGCCCCGACUCAGCAUCCCCUGCUCUUCUAUCACAGACGUCCGGACAACCACAGCCCUGGAGAUGCCUGACCGGGAGAACACGUUUGUGGUUAAGGUGGAAGGUCCAUCCGAGUAUAUCAUGGAGACAGUGGAUGCCCAGCAUGUGAAGGCCUGGGUGUCUGACAUCCAAGAAUGCCUGAGCCCAGGACCCUGCCCUGCUACCAGUCCCCGCCCCAUGACCCUCCCUCUGGCCCCUGGGACCUCAUUCCUUACAAGGGAGAACACAGACAGCCUGGAGCUGUCCUGCCUGAAUCACUCGGAGAGUCUACCCAGCCAGGACCUGCUGCUUGGACCCAGCGAGAGCAAUGACCGCCUGUCGCAGGGGGCAUAUGGGGGCCUCUCAGACCGCCCCUCGGCAUCCAUCUCCCCCAGCUCUGCCUCCAUUGCCGCCUCCCAUUUUGACUCGAUGGAACUGCUUCCCCCAGAGUUGCCCCCCCGCAUCCCCAUUGAAGAGGGACCCCCAACAGGGACAGUUCAUCCCCUCUCAGCCCCCUACCCUCCCUUGGACACUCCGGAAACAGCCACAGGGUCCUUCCUGUUCCAGGGGGAGCCAGAGGGCGGUGAGGGGGACCAGCCCCUCUCAGGGUAUCCUUGGUUCCACGGGAUGCUCUCUCGGCUCAAGGCUGCACAGUUGGUGCUGACUGGCGGCACUGGCUCCCACGGUGUCUUCCUGGUGCGCCAGAGUGAGACAAGGCGGGGUGAAUACGUCCUCACCUUCAACUUCCAGGGCAAGGCCAAGCACCUGCGUUUGUCGCUGAACGAGGAGGGUCAGUGCCGGGUCCAGCACCUGUGGUUCCAGUCCAUUUUCGAUAUGCUCGAGCACUUCCGGGUGCACCCCAUCCCUUUGGAGUCGGGAGGCUCCAGUGAUGUUGUCCUUGUCAGCUAUGUCCCAUCCUCCCAGCGACAGCAGGGCCGGGAGCAGGCUGGGAGCCAUGCGGGGGUGUGCGAGGGAGAUGGAUGCCACCCCGAUGCCUCCUGCACCCUCAUGCCCUUCGGAGCGAGUGACUGUGUAACCGACCACCUCCCAUGACCCACCCCAGCCCCCUGAACCCCCUUCAUGGACAGAUCCCCCACAGCCUGGGGCAGAAGAGGCGUCGAGGGCGCCAGAAGUGGCGGCAGCAGCAGCCGCAGCAGCCAAAGAGAGGCAAGAGAAAGAGAAAGCGGGCGGUGGAGGGGUCCCGGAAGAGCUGGUCCCCGUGGUUGAGCUGGUCCCCGUGGUUGAAUUGGAAGAGGCCAUAGCCCCAGGCUCAGAGGCCCAGGGCGCUGGGUCUGGUGGGGACGCGGGGGUGCCCCCAAUGGUGCAGCUGCAGCAGUCACCACUAGGGGGUGAUGGAGAGGAAGGGGGCCACCCCAGGGCCAUUAACAACCAGUACUCCUUCGUGUGAGCCAACCCCACCCGCUCCACCCUUUUUAAACCCCCCAGCCCUGCUCGUGAGAUUGGGCUGGGUAGGGACAGAGGAGGCCGAAAUCCCUCCCCCAUGCUUCCUGACCCUUGUUGGCCAAGGGCAUCUUUGAUGGUACAAGCAGAGGCUCGGGAGAGGCUCCCGUCACACACUACAGGUCCCCUCCCCAGGGCAGGGGAUUUGGGCUCCAUGAGCUCCUUGAGGGGCUCUUCUGGUCAGCCCCACCCUGGGGGCCAUUUCCCCAUUAACUACCCCCAGCCCGAGGCAGGGUGAGGGGGAAGGGCUGUCAGUUACAUUAAGGUGGUUGUUGUUGUUGUUUUAAACAAAAUGGAGAAGCAUAAAUAAAUAAAAAGGUUUAUCUCGGUUC